GCAUUUGAGAAGGCGCCUGUGAGGGUCGCUCCUCAGCCGCCGCGCUCCCACUCCGCGUCCCCACUCCGCGCCGCCGCGCCUCUGCCAGCCCCGAAGGUGGACGUGAAGCUCCAACACCUCGACUUCUGGGCCCGCCUCCAUGGCCAGGUCCCGGGACUGCUGGACUGGGACAUGGGGAACGAGCUCUUUCUGGCCUUCACCACAUCUCACCUCCCCUUAGCGGAGCAGAAACUUGCCAGGUAUAAACUCCGAAUUGUUAAGCCACCAAAAUUACCCCUAGAGAAAAAACCCAACCCUGAUAAGGAUGGUCCAGAUUAUGAGCCCAACCUCUGGAUGUGGGUAAAUCCCAACAUUGUGUAUCCCCCUGGAAAGCUGGAGGUCUCAGGACGUAGGAAGAGGGAGGACCUGACAAGCACACUCCCCUCCUCUCAGCCACCCCAGAAGGAGGAAGAUGCCAGCUGCUCAGAGGCCGCAGGGGUGGAAUCACUGUCCCAGUCCUCCAGCAAGCGGUCUCCCCCUCGGAAGCGGUUUGCCUUUUCCCCCAGCACCUGGGAGCUCACAGAAGAGGAGGAGGCUGAGGACCAGGAAGACAGCUCCUCUAUGGCUCUCCCAUCCCCUCACAAAAGGGCCCCCCUCCAGAGUCGGAGGCUUCGGCAAGCCAGCAGCCAGGCGGGGAGGCUCUGGUCCCGGCCCCCUCUCAAUUACUUCCACCUAAUUGCCCUGGCAUUAAGAAACAGUUCCCCCUGUGGCCUCAACGUGCAACAGAUCUACAGUUUCACUCGAAAGCACUUCCCCUUUUUCCGGACGGCCCCGGAAGGCUGGAAGAAUACUGUCCGUCACAAUCUCUGUUUUCGAGACAGCUUUGAGAAAGUGCCUGUCAGCAUGCAGGGCGGGGCCAGCACACGGCCUCGAUCUUGCCUCUGGAAGUUGACCGAGGAGGGACACCGCCGCUUUGCGGAGGAGGCCCGCGCCUUGGCUUCCACUCGGCUAGAAAGUAUCCAACAGUGCAUGAGCCAGCCAGGUGUGAAGACUUGUUGUGCGUGGGCCCAAGGGGAAGAGACCUGAGGAUCCUGACCCAAGGCCAAGUGUGGAAGCCUGGGUCACACCGUGGGGGUGGGGGAAUGCAUCUUCUAUAGGAAACAGGGAGAU